GCUUUAGGGUUCACCUGGGAAAAACACCAGCCACAGACACAGCUGCGGCUGUUUCUCCAAAGAGCUUUUCAGGAGGCUUCCUGUUGGCGCAUUUCCUUAAGCGGGGCCGGGGGCAGGUAGGAAGAGGGGCCAGCAGGCAGGAAGGCUGAAGGCUGCAUUCCUGUGAGACGUUCCUCAGUGCCUAAUUUACACUUUCCAUAAGGUAAGGCGAAUGACCGGCGAGGGAAAGGGAGUAAAGGAAGAGUCAGUUACACAGGCGUCUCUGGGUAGGUGGAGGAAGGAGUCUCCGUUCUGUACACGGAAGAUGAGCGUGUAGGGGACACGAUCAGUGUGGAAUCCACACACCUCAGCUUCAGGCGCUGGACUUAGACUGUAGACCUGUAGUCAGCACCGAAUGCCCUGUUUAUGGGAGGACAGCAGAGAAUUUACUCGUGAUUGAUCUGUGGGGCAGCCCUCCCCAGAAACCGGAGGCCUUUACCUUUCCACGGGGAUCUGGCUGGAGCAGGAAGUUAGUAACAGUAAUUCAUUUGGAAGAAGGGGCUGCAGUGACCUUCCCUUUUGCAUAAGAAGUUUGGGGGUCCUGAGAUUUUUAUAAUUUCCCUUUACAGGUUCAUAUUACAGACAAGUAACUGCCAGAGGUUUUGGAAAAAAAUAAGAUGAAACAAUAAUAAUCUAAUAAAUAAACGUUAAUCAUCUAUUCACAUUUUUUAUGUAUAAUGAUAUGCUAUUGUGAUUAUGAAAUAUCUGACAUUUUCUGGUGCAGAGAAUACUUUGAGAAGCAUUGCUUUAGGCCUAGGGAGAUACACAGAUAUGAUACAGAUAUUAAUACGUACCAAACUAUGUAAAUACAUACUAUGCAUGUGUGUGUAUGUCAUAUAUACAUACAUAUGUGCACACAUGUUGUAAUGUGUAUUGACAUAACUUGUUAAAUAAAAAAUUAUCUUGUCUCUGGUGAAACAUACUAAAUAUCCACGUAAGUUGUGACGGGUUUAAUUUCAUCAGUAGAUGAGCGGCCGCACAUGGAAGAACUUUAAAACUGUCGUGACUUGGGUGCAUUGCUAUCACUCAGUACCUUCUAGAGACUGGAAGCACGUCCUUCCUGGAGCACUGGGCCUUUUCGUGUUGGAGAUCUUGGUGAUUGACUGUAUUUGCCUCUCUGCCUGUGGAGCCCAAAACCUGGGUUUUAGGCUAUAAGUUUAGUGUUUCUCAACCUGACUCUGAAGAGGAAGAGGCAGCUGCCAUCUGAGUUCUUCCUUAUGGGCUUAGAAGAGAAUGUUUCAGGAUUACUAUCUGUCCUUGUGAGUAUGAGUGUGAGUGUGGUGUGUGUAUGUGUGUCAUGUGUGUCAUAUGUGUUGUGUUUUGUGCGUUGUGUAUGGUGUGUGUGGCAUGUGUGUUGUAUGUGUGGUGUGUGUAUGUGUGGCAUGUAUGUUCUGUGUUGUGUGCCUGUGUGGCAUGUGUGUUGUGUGUGCAGCAUGUGUGUUGUGUGUGGUGUGCAUGUGUGGCAUGUGUUGUGUGCAUGUUGUGUGUGACGUGUGUUGUGUGUGUUGCAUGUGGCAUGUUUGUUGUGUUUUGUGUGUGUGGUGUGUGUUGUGUGUGUCUGGCAUGUGUAUGUGUUGUGUGGGGCAAGUGUGUUGUGUGUGUUGUGUGCAUGGUAUGUGUGUUCUGUGUGUGGCAUGUGUAUUGUGUGUGGUGUGUGUGACAUGUGUGGUGUGUGUGUGGCAUCUAUGUUGAGUGUGCAUGUGGCAUGCGUGUGUCAUUCACAUUGUGUAGCAUAUGUGUUGUGUGGCAUGGGGGUUGUGAUGUGUGUGGCGUGUGUUGUGCGCCUGUGUGUGGUGUGUGACAUGUGUGGUGUGUGCUUUGUGUCAUGUGUGUUGUGUGUGAUACGUAUUUGGUGUGUGGCAUGUGUGGUGUGUGUGGCAUGUGUUUGGUGUGUGACGUGGUGUGUGUGGUGUGUGCUCUGUGGCAUGUGUGUUGUGUAUGUGGCAUGUGUGGUGUGUCGUGUGUUGUGUGGCAUGUGUGGUCUCUGGCAUGUGUGUUGUGCAUGUGUGUGGUGUGUGUGGCAUGUGUGUGGCAUGUGUAGUGUGUGUGCAUUUGGCAUGUGUGUCAUGUGUGUUGUGUGAUGUGUUGGCUGUGUGUCUGGCAUGUGUGUUGUGUGUAGUGUGUGUGUAUGUGUGUGACGUGUGCUGUGUGGCAUGUGUGUUGUGUGUUGUGCACUGUGUGGCAUAUGUAUUUGUGUGGUGUGUGCGGCAUGUGUGUGUUGUGUGCGAUGUGUGCUGUGUGGUGUGUAUGUGGCAUGUGUGUUGUGUGUGUGACAUGUGUGUGCUGUGUGGCAUGUGUGUUGUGUGUGGUAUGUGCUGUGUGGCAUGUGUGUUGUGUGUGUCGUGUGUGACGUGUGUUGUGUCAUAUGUGCGUGAUGUGUGUGCUGUGUGGGAUGUAUGUUGUGUAUGUGUUGUGUGUGUGGUGUGUGUUUAUUGGUGUGUGUGGUGUUGCUGUGUGGUAUGUUGUGUGUGUUGUGUGUGGUCUGUGCUGUGUGGCAUUUGUGUUGUGUGUGUGUUGUGUGUGUGUGCAGCAUGUGUGUUGUGCGUGUGUUGUGCUGUGUGCUGUGUGGCAUGUGUGUUGUGCGUUGUGUGUGUUGUGUGCUGUGUCGCAUGCGUGUUGUGUGUGUUGUGUGCUGUGUGGCAUGCGUGUUGUGUGUGUUGUGUGCUGUGUGGCAUGUGUGUUGUGUAUGUCCCAGUUCUCUGUCUUCAGGCGGUUGGGAUCCCCUGUGCUGGCCCCGCUGUGCAGGUGCAGGUGUGCAGGGCGGGGCUGGGAGCUCCUGGGGACAUGGGGACGCCCUUGAAGUCCGCCCUGUGCCCCGUGAGGAGUGGGGUUUUGGGGUUUUGGGUUUCGCGCUGGGCUGCGUUUCUGCAGGAGCCAGGCCUCUUCAUGCUCUGCGGCGACAGCCGCUGGGGUGGGGCUACGGGGAAGUCGCGCUGCCCCUCGUCUGAGCGUGGGCCAGGGCCCAGGUGGUGACCAAGGCCCGGCGCAGUGGCCCCGGAGCGUGGAGGGGCAGCUGCUGGGCGGCCUCCCGGGGGAGGGUGACGGCUUCACCCGCCAACGCUGCCUCCCUCCUGGGAUUAGGCCGGAGGAAUCUUGGAUCGCCCGAGGCUGGUGCUCAGCCUCCUUCCCCCAUCCCACCUCCACCACCCGGCGACCCCCGUAGACUUGAUUGGCAGGCCCUGCCCCGACCCCUACCCCUCCAGGUCCCCGCCUCGGUGCCUCGGUGCCCGGCUCCGGGCCACUCCUGCAGGCCCUGCCUAGGGCAGCCGGCGGUGCCUGGAGGCGGGCUCGCCCCGGCUGCUCCACGCCCAGGCCGGUCCCUGGCAUUUCAGCCAGUGGGAGGGCGUCCCCGCCGCCCCCGUGCCUCUCCGCAGGGGCUGCGCCGCGUCCCCGGGCCUCUCCCUCCGCCGUGGCCUGGUCUGCCUGCUCCAGGGCGCAGCUGCGCCCGCUUCAGCGCCUCCCGGGUCUGCGUGGCCUGCUCGGCUCAGAGGCCUCCACCACGGUCCGCUCCCUGCCGGACGCCGCGCUGCUGUGGCCGCGGUGGUUCUGUGGCUGUGAGGGCCGUUUCUGUCCGUCCACACCGCCUUCCCUCUGCAGAUUUCCUCUGCAGAGGCCCGGAGUUACCAGCAAGGUCUGACGCAGCAGAGUGCAGAAACGGCCUCCCUGUCUGUCAAAGUGGCCUCCCGAGGACACCCAGCGAGGCCACCAGAUCAUCACGUGGAGUAUCGGUGGCCUUAUUAAAACAAAAACAACAACUCCACAGCCCGGCGAGCGUGUGAAAUCAUCACCACAACCAAGCCAAGUGCAUCCAUCGCUCAGGCAGUCACCAUGGUGUGAGUGCGGUGAGACGGCUUUGAUCUGGCUCUCAGCCACUUCUGAUGCUCCUGGUACCUGCAGUCACCACGCUGCACCCAGGCUUCUGUGUGUGUUCAUCCCACAGCUGCAGCAGCCCAAAGGGAUGAGAAGAUGGAUAUGGCCCGGAGAUAAUGCACACCUCUCGUGGGGACAGUGUCCCCAUCCCCCUCCGGCUGCACUGAAGACCUGGAGCAAUGGCUGCCAUCCAUGCGCGAGGACCCCUCGGAGGUUCCACCUGCACAGACCUUGCUAAGGGUGAGGUGAUUACUAGAAGGAGCACCUUUUCUAGUUAAAAUCUAACUAGAUUCUCCUUGGCAACUUGUCUUACAGAAACAGGUAUAGACUAUCACCUUGCCCAGCUGGGCGCAUCUUCGGAGGGAGGCCUGGGGCCACGUGCACCUAAUGAAGGUGCCUGGGAGGGGGCUGGCUUUCCACUCAGCAAAUGCUUUCUUACAGAAAGACUGUGGGGAGAGUCCGUUUUCUUAGAGCCGUAUGAAGAAAUCCUAAAAACCAACUGCCCAAUCUCAACUCGUAACAGGGAACCUGGGGAGUGACAUCAGAGAUUCCCAAUGUUUUCCUCCUCGUUGAUCCCUGCGAUGAAGGCACUUGCCCAUGUGUAUUCUGUAGUAGGAGUUUGCAUUCUGAAACUGGUCUUUAUUAAAGAACAAACACAUUAUUUACAAA